AGCUGGAUUCAGCGUGUCCGCGACCUCACCUUUAGGUCCUGUGAGGUCGGUGGAAUCCUGGGGUCCUCCAAAUCUACCAGGCCAUCUCCCCAGUUUCCCAGUUCUUCCUGCGUGCGGGCGAGAGUGGUUGGGCCCUCGGGAACCCACUCAGAGCGAGGCUAAAUUUACGGAGGGACUUUCUGUUAGCAGCAUGAGGGCCUGUGGUUAGACCUAUAGAGGUAUUUCCUUUGAUUUAAGCCAGAAAGUCCUGAGAGCGGAUCGGGGAGCAUUUGCGGAUCGGUCACUUUUUCCUCCUUUCUGAGUCUCUUAUCCCCUACCACAGGGACGGCCCAGGUGGCAGGAUGUCCUGGUCUGGCCUUCUCCAUGGCCUCAACACGUCCCUAACUUGUGGCCCAGCUCUGGUUCCCCGGCUCUGGGCUACCUGCUCCAUGGCUACCCUGAACCAGAUGCACCGCCUGGGGCCCCCCAAGCGGCCGCCUCGGAAGCUGGGCCCCACGGAAGGCCGGCCGCAGCUGAAGGGUGUGGUCCUGUGCACGUUUACCCGCAAGCCGAAGAAGCCCAACUCAGCCAAUCGCAAGUGCUGUCGAGUGCGGCUCAGCACUGGCCGCGAGGCCGUCUGCUUCAUCCCUGGGGAGGGCCACACCCUGCAGGAGCACCAGAUUGUCCUUGUGGAGGGCGGCCGCACCCAGGACCUGCCAGGCGUCAAGCUCACCGUUGUGCGUGGCAAGUACGACUGUGGCCACGUGCAGAAGAAGUGACGGCUGGGGGCACAGUGGGCUGGGCGCCCCUGCAGAACAUGAACCUUCCGCUCCUGGCUGCCACAGGGUCCUCCGAUGCUGGCCUUUGCGCCUCUAGAGGCAGCCACUCAUGGAUUCAAGUCCUGGCUCCGCCUCUUCCAUCAGGACCACUAUUAAGCCAUAGGAGUCCUGGGGGUGCAAAGGGUGCCCCUCUGUCAACACCCUUGGCUCCUGUGUUUAGAGGGGUGGCCUGAAGGACCUUUUCUGCUGGGACAAGACACUGUACUGCCCUCUGCUGGGAAGGGGUUUUAAUAAACAGACCCUGGCGCUUGUGAUGUAAA